AUGGCUGUGGGACCCCGACGCAACCACCUUCCCCUAUGGCCUUCAGCUGCCAUCGAGCAACGACGGCCUGGCUGUUGGAGGAUGCGGUUUGCAGCCUGUGAUUCUGGGACCACCUGUGCAGGGCGGCGGCCGAGGGCAGCGCGCUGGACCCGCGCCCCUCGCCAGCCGCCGGGCCGGCUUGAUUACUGCCCUCCCCGGCCCGACCGCGGGCACCUGAACGCCGACAGCAGAGCACGGCGACCUCUGGGGCUAGCGCGCAAGGUCAGACCAGGUCCAGGGCUUCCCUGCCCUCUGCGGGGACCCUGGAGCACCGACAGCCCCACCUCCCCACCUCCAAGCCCCACUCCCAUCUCCCACCAGGGGCAAGAAGGUGGAGGGAGGCCAGCGGACACAACCCGAGGACCCAGGCGGCCUGCGCCUCCGCGCCAAGCCUGGGGGUGGCCGAUGGCAAGGGAGGCCCGGAGUAACCCAGCCAGUGAGGGCCAGGCUGCAGCUAACACUGAUCCUGCUUCUGGGGCCGACACAGGCCUGGUCUGUGAUGGUGGGACUUACCAGAGCUUAGUGGAAAGAAAAUCCCUGAGUCUGGGGCUUCAGGAGUCUCAGGCUGGGGAGGGACUCUGGUAGCACCCAUGAGGGGACACGUGGUUGUGCCCCAGGGAGGCCAGCCACCUGCUCUCCACUUGCCCUUGGAUAGAAAAGGGAGGUGGAUUUAACCUGCUCCAGGAGACAUGACUUUUAUUUUUAAGACUUUUUAAAAUUGAAGUUAAGCACACACACAGAACACUGCACAAAUCAAAGUGUACAACUGAAAGAAUUUGCACAUGCUUUGCAUACCUGUGCAACCAGCACCCAAAUUAAAAAACAGCACCUCACCGGCACCCAGAAGCCCCUCGAGACCCCUUCCACCUACUGUUCCCGAGUCCAGCCUCUCUCCUGACUCAGCCCGCAGGCGCUCUGGCCUGCUUCUGAACUGUGUGUAGAUGGAGCCAUACAGUGGGUGCCGUUUUGCGUCUGGUUUCUUUUGCUGCAUAUUAUGUUUGUGAGGUUUGUCAGUACUCUCACAGGCAGUCAAGGGCUGUUCGUACCCAUUGCUGGUGGCUUGCCAUUGUGUGGCUCUGUUAAAAUGUAUUCACCCAUGUUACUGCUAAUGGACAUUUGGGGAGGUUCCAGUUCCUGGCUAUGGUGAAUAGUGCCACUAUGAACAUUCUAGUUCCUGUGUAUUGUGAACAUAUGAAUGCAUUUCUGUUGGGUGAAUACCCAGGGCAGGGAUGACGGGGCCCGGCUGUGUGUCUGCUCAGCUUUGGAAGAUACAGGAAUGUUACUUUUUAAUCAUUUCAGUAAGAAUGAUUUUUCAAGGUAA